GCUGCAGGGAGGGUCUUCUUGGGGCCGUCGUGCCCCGCCCCAGUGCGGCCGGGGCGCGGGUUCGAGCUGCUGCUCGGCAAGCCUGGGUGUCUAGGGCAUGAGCGGAGUGUGGGGGGCCGGCGGGCCUCGGUGCCAGGAGGCGCUCGCGGUCCUCGCCUCGCUGUGCCGGGCCCGGCCGCCCCCUCUCGGGCUGGACGUGGAGACUUGUCGGAGCUUCGAGCUGCAGCCCCCAGAGCGGAGUCCCAGCGCGGCAGGCGCAGGCACCUCUGUCAGCCUCCUCGCAGUUGUAGUUAUUGUGUGUGGCGUGGCCCUGGUGGCAGUUUUUCUCUUUCUCUUUUGGAAGCUGUGCUGGAUGCCCUGGAGGAACAAGGAGGCCUCCAGUCCCUCUUCUGCUAAUCCCCCCUUGGAAGCCCUCCAGAGCCCCAGCUUCAGAGGCAACAUGGCGGACAAGCUGAAGGACCCCAGCACCCUGGGCUUCCUGGAGGCGGCCGUGAAGAUCAGCCACACGUCCCCAGAUAUCCCAGCUGAGGUGCAGAUGUCGGUCAAGGAGCACAUCAUGCGUCACACCCGGCUGCAGCGGCAAACUACAGAGCCAGCGUCAUCCACCAGGCACACGUCCUUCAAGCGCCACCUGCCAAGGCAGAUGCAUGUCUCCAGUGUAGACUAUGGCAAUGAGCUUCCACCAGCAGCAGAGCAGCCCACCAGCAUUGGCCGCAUCAAGCCUGAGCUCUACAAGCAGAAGUCGGUGGAUGGGGAGGAUGCCAAGUCUGAGGCCACCAAGAGCUGCGGGAAGAUCAACUUCAGCCUACGCUACGAUUACGAGACCGAGACCCUGAUUGUGCGUAUCCUGAAGGCUUUUGACCUCCCUGCCAAGGACUUUUGUGGAAGCUCUGACCCUUAUGUCAAGAUCUACCUCCUGCCUGACCGCAAAUGCAAGCUGCAGACCCGGGUGCACCGCAAGACCCUGAACCCCACCUUUGAUGAGAACUUCCACUUCCCUGUGCCCUAUGAGGAGCUGGCUGACCGCAAGCUGCAUCUCAGUGUCUUCGACUUUGACCGCUUCUCCCGCCAUGACAUGAUUGGCGAGGUCAUCCUGGACAACCUCUUUGAGGCCUCUGACCUGUCUCGGGAAACCUCCAUCUGGAAGGAUAUCCAAUAUGCCACAAGUGAAAGCGUGGACUUGGGAGAGAUCAUGUUCUCCCUUUGCUACCUGCCCACUGCAGGCAGGCUCACCCUCACAGUGAUUAAGUGUCGGAACCUCAAGGCGAUGGACAUCACAGGCUAUUCAGAUCCCUAUGUGAAAGUGUCCUUGCUCUGUGAUGGGCGGAGGCUGAAGAAGAAGAAAACAACCAUAAAGAAAAACACUCUCAAUCCUGUCUACAAUGAGGCCAUCAUCUUUGACAUUCCCCCGGAAAACAUGGAUCAAGUCAGCCUGCUCAUCUCAGUCAUGGACUAUGAUCGAGUGGGCCACAAUGAGAUCAUAGGAGUCUGUCGUGUGGGGAUCACUGCUGAAGGCCUGGGCAGGGACCACUGGAACGAGAUGCUGGCAUACCCCCGGAAGCCCAUCGCACACUGGCACUCCUUGGUGGAGGUAAAGAAAUCCUUCAAAGAGGGAAACCCUCGGUUGUGAUUUCAUUCACGUGGAUGCUGCAAGCAGAGAGACUGCCACCUGGAGUUAGGAUGGCAGGGCCGAGCUGCUAGCUUCGACAGUGAGAGCUCGUGCCCAUCUCCGAAACCACCUCCAACACCAUGAGAUGUGCAGCCAAAUAACACAAAUGGGACUCAGCAAUGUUCUCUUUGCACUUGUUCAACCGUCUAAACAGUGUUGUGCAGUCGCAGUGGCGGCAGCAGCGGCAGCCGUCCGUCACUCCAGAGUCUUACCUGCUCCUGUGUAGGUCAAAGCUGAGACACUUGUCAUGUGGUCAGAUCUGUCUUAGUCUUUUGUGUCUCCCAAGGUGAUGUUUUUGUGGUUUUUCACUUUUUAUGGGUCUGCUGGUAAGAAAAGGGAAAAAAAAAAAGAGUAGGAAAAGACAAAGGGUGGAAAGCCCAGAAGUUGGUUCUAGAAAAUACAAGGUACAGUUUUUUGGAAAGAGGUGGAUUGAGUUUCUGAAAUGCUGCGUCUCCAGCAAGCUCCACAACCCUGGAAAAGGAGGAGGCGUGGUGGGACUGCGGCUGCAUUUUCAGUGCCCUGCAGGAAUGGGGUGAAUCCAUGGAAGAGCCUUUGUGAGGUGAAUUACUAGUCUUUGAAGCUCUUCGCUGGCAGGACAUAAACCACGCUGGGACCCUCAGUCCCGUGUUGAAAUCACAAGACCUCUGAGGCGCUUGUGAGCCUUCAGCUGAUGUGCAGGGUUCCUCGCUCCCCUUCCUCGCUGGCUUUCCCCAUGAAUUGAAAACGUCUUGAUUCCUCAUGGGAACUUAGUCACUUUCUUUAGGAAUGAUUCAGUUCAGCCGAAACUAAACACGCCAUAUGUUUUCUGAUGCGCCACAGUUAAUGAUCACAUUUGUUUGAAAACAGGAUCUUUGUCCUCAGAAAUAAUCUUGAUUGUAAAGUAAGAGAGAAACAUAUGUUCUGGAAUGAUUUCUGCAUUAUACAUAGCUUUAUAAUUCCAUGAAGUAUCAAGCUGCUGUUUAAAAUGCCUAAACAGAUUAAAGAAAAACCUAGAUUAAAUGUUCUUUUCCAAAUGGGGAGUUUUGAAAUCCAAAUAGCAGUUUGAGUCCAUCUUUCUAUGAAGAGUAUGUUUUUGAUUGAAACCGAGUCAGCGUAAGCCUAUUUCAGCCCCUUUGGCUCUUUGACAAUAUUCAUCUUAAACUUUAGUUCUAUAAAUUACUAAGUACUUCAGUGUUGUUUGUUUCAGUGGUUGUGAGGGUUUCUUGUUUCCUUUAGAUCUUUACCUUAGGCCAAACUCAGUUUAGGAAAAAAAAAAUUGUUUGAACUAUUCUGUGUUGUAAUAGCACAUUUCUGUUGAGUUAAUAGUGGUCUUCCCACCAACCCCUAAAACCAGGUUGAUUUGCUCAAUCUCAGUUUGUAUAACCCCAGUAAGCGCAUGGAGGUGAGUUUCUACUUCGACUUGUGGCGACACAGUGCCAGUUUCCUGAGCUGUGUGUACUACUUGCAAGAGGCAAGUCUGCUGAAGAACCCCUUCUUUUAACAGUGGAAAAUCAAGAACAGAAAAUCUGUUCACACACCUGUGUCUUAUUCUUUAUAUAUGCUACAUGGUAGAGGAGCAGCGACCAAUAAAGUAUCCCUCAUUUUAAACCAAGUUGUCAGAUUUCUCUGCUGAUAGAACGCUGCAUAGUAUCUUCUAGCCCUAAAAAUGACCAGGUUGGGCAUGAGUUAACAGGAUAUUGUGGCAAAAGGAAUUUUCUGCUUAGAAAAGUAAAUGUAGAUAAACCUAAACUCCACCCUGUACUGAGCCUUAGGCUAGGGACUCAUGUGUAAAGAUGACUUUUCUCCCCAGAUAUCUUGUCAUUGACAGGCCUUCCUAGUCUGGUAGUCCUACAUUUGGGUGUUCUCCUGAGAGUGAGAAAAAACCCAAGGUCAUGACAAGAUUCCUGGCAGGUGACAGACUUCAUUAUGAUUCUGACUCUAGACUGACCCCAUCAAGAUAGUCGUUUCCGUCAGUGAACAGAUGCUGAAGGCCUUGCCAUUACAAAGGAGACAACUGAGUUCCCUGGGUCAUAAGGAGUCCAGAAAUUAGUGUGAGAAGGUCCUUCUGGAAGUGAACUCAAAAUUCAUGUCCAGCUGUCAUCGUUAAACCCUUAGGCAGGUGAGUAUAACCCAUUCUAACCUCUUGGAGAAGGGAGUGUGAUCAAUGUGAAUCACAAUAGUAUUGCUCAUCUGAGACAUUCCUCUUAUAUCCAAGCAGCUAUCUCCCAUGAGUGAACAUCCCAGUGGUUUCAGAAAAUCAUGUCCUGAACAGAUUCUAGCCAGCCCCACACCACCCUGGCCAACUGCAACCGCUGCUGCUCUAGCAGUCUGGGUCAAUUCCUACAGGCUUGGGAGCCCACCCCAGGGAGGCUUUUAUCUCCUGCAGCCUCAUCCCCAGCACCCUCAAGGUAGACUACUCCUCAGCCUGAAUCAUGAAUGAAACCUGAACAUCUGCCAACUUCAUUAUCUAGCCCAGUAUCUCUUCCCUCACAGAGAAGAAGAAAAUGAAAUACAAAGUUGAUCCAUUUGUUGGCUUUCUCUGGCCGGAGAAACCUCUCGGGUUGUUGCUGUGAGCUUUGAUGAAGUUGUGAUAACCAGGGCCAUUUGCACAUAGGUUUUUUUAAAAAACAUGAAAAGUUCCCUUCUCCUUUAUUUAGCAGUGUUUCCGGGCUGAAAGACGCCCUCCUCCCCCUCUGCGCUUACCCAGGACGUUAAUUAAUUGCACUGUCAUUUAAAAUAUUAUGUUGUUAAUUACUCGUUUGUGUCUUCCCACCCGUGUCACAGCCUGGAGUUUUUAUUCAAUUAAAUCUCUGUCUCUUGCCCA